GCAGCCGAGUUCAGCCGGGAGCAGAGCGAACCGCACCGGCCCGAGCGGAGCGCCGCACGUUCCCAACCGCGAGGCCAGGUACCGCUUCGGGAGUUCAUCCCACCCGCACAGGGGAAUCGGGUGGGCCGAGCCCUACUGUCCACCCUCCUGUCCGUAGCCGGGCUCUGGGCAGCUCUCCUCUACCGUCCUGACCCGGGCAGGCGCCCCAGCCUCCGGCGAGCCAAAGCCCCGCGCGCUCCAGGCGCUGGUCUUGGGGACCUGCCAGUCGGGACUCAGCGCCGAGCUUAAGCAGGGCCCUGGGGGUACCGGGAGGGACACGUCGUCGCCUUAGGGCCUCUCGGCGGGGCUGCGAGGUACAGCAGGAGGUCGGCGGCACCCGGGGCUGGGACCACAGGACGCCUUGUUGGGGGCUCGGGCGGCACACCACAGGCUUCCUGAGGCAGGGCCCAUGGGGCAGGCUGGAGAGGGCCCGAGGGGAGGACCCAAGAGGGGCCUGGAGCAGUCCCUGGAGCGCUGCCCCGACGGGCGCCUGACAGGCAGAGCAGCCCGGCUGGCACGAUGGGAAUCCGGGUAUAUUUAUCUCGGCUGCUCCGGACAAGGGCUUGAGGGCAGAUCGGGCCGGGCCGCCUGAGGGGCCGCGGGGUACAUGCUGGUCCCAGAGCCGGUGCCAUUUGCAGAGGAGCCAGCGGGCACAGCGGGCGCAGGGCGCGAGUGGCUCCCUGACCUGAGGCCGGGGCGCCGUGCGAGCUCCUCCCCACCUGGCGCUGGGUAGGGUGUAAGUUAGAGCCCGCGCAGCGCACGGCGGAGAGAAGGAACCAAGACUUGGUUUGCAAGAGCCCGCCCCCGCCCGGUUGGCCCCUUCGAUUGGCCACAGCAAAUGCGUGCGUUUGUUUACACCCAGGCAGGGGGAGGCCAGGGGAGGGACCUGCGGGGACCCGCCCUUUUCCCCCCACGGGGACCUGAGUCCUGAGUCCAGGUAUGGGCUCUCAAACAGGUCUGAGAAAGGCUAAGUCAAAGGCUCUUGAGCCCUGAGGAACACCAUGGAGGACUUCCCCACUCAUGCCCAUCCUUCCUUCAGCCUGCCAACCCUGUCCUUUCUUCCAUGACCGACUCUGGCCACAGAGCUGCCCCUGGAAAAGGCCCUUGGACCUUUCACCCCUUCCUGUUCUGUUCUGUAAAAGGUCUGGGAUGGGGCUCAUUUCCUUCUGGAAAGGAAGCACAUCCCUCGGGGCUCUCAGUCUGGGGGAUAGAAAGCUAAAGAGACCCAAAGAUGGUUCCAUUUUGAAUGGGGGAAAUUCGGCACAGCCACGGUACCCUUCCUGCAAGAAGCAUCACUGACGGGAGGGAUCAGGACUGGAAGAGGCCAAGCCUGGCACGUCUCUGAGAGGGCUGGAAUGACUGAAACCAGAAAUGGGAAUCUGAUUUCUUGACAUUGGGAGCAGGGGGCUGAAUCUCUGGGGAGGGUAGGAGUCUGUAUCUCAGAAUUUUGUUCUGCCUGGGCCCAUGGGACCCAUGUCUUCGCUGGCUUCUCAAGCCACUCCUUGUUGUGUGCUGGUUUUUUUGGCCCAUGUCACAAAUGGUCCCCACACCAGUCCAGGGCUCCAGGUUGCCAGAUCAUGACAACUGGUUGCUCCUGUCCUUGUGCCACUGCCCUAGCAAGUAGCCUUGAAGCCCUGGACAGUUGGAGAAACUGAGGCACAACAAGACUGGCUGGGUGGUUCAUGGUCUCUGGGUUGAGUCAGAGAAGGAUUUUAAGCUGAACUGGACACACCCUGGAAGUCUGGGCUGGGUGUGAGGACAAGCAUCCAGUUUGAGAGGGAAACAUAUUUGGAGGGGAGUGGUGUGGGGUGGGCCACCAGGGAGGUGCAGUUUUGGUGUCUCUGUGAACAGAAAGCUGAGGUGGAAUGUGCAGUCUAUGCUAUAGUAGAAUUGGGACCCAGUGGGAGGAUGUUUUAGUGUAGACAUGGCCAGGGGCCAGGCCUCACUUGGAGCAGGUAAGAGGGCUUGCCGAGGGCCUCAAAUGCAUUCCAUUCGUUUAUUUUUUUUAUUUUUUUCAUUUUUUGAGGUGGGGUCUCACUCUGUUGCCCAAGCUGGAGUGCAGUGGCACAAUCUCGCCUCACUGCAACCGCCGCCUCCCAGGCCCAAGCAAUUCUCCCACCUCAGCCUUCUGAGUAGCCAGGACCGCAAGUGUGCAACAUCAAGCCUGGACAUCUGACUGUUGGUGUGAGACCAGUGCUCCUGGUGGUGUGCCCUGAGCCAUGGAGGCGCCUUUGCAGACAGAGAUGGUGGAGCUGGUGCCCAAUGGCAAACACUCAGAGGGGCUGCUCCCGGUCAUCACCCCCAUGGCAGGCAACCAGAGGGUCGAGGACCCUGCACGGAGCUGUAUGGAGGGCAAGAGCUUCCUACAGAAAAGUCCCAGCAAGGAGCCACACUUCACUGACUUCGAGGGGAAGACAUCAUUCGGGAUGUCAGUGUUCAACCUCAGCAAUGCCAUCAUGGGCAGCGGCAUCCUGGGACUCGCCUAUGCCAUGGCCAAUACGGGCAUUAUCCUUUUCCUGUUCCUGUUGACAGCUGUCGCCUUGCUCUCCAGCUACUCCAUCCACCUGCUACUCAAGUCCUCAGGGGUCGUGGGCAUCCGUGCCUAUGAGCAGCUGGGCUACCGUGCCUUUGGGACCCCAGGAAAGCUGGCAGCAGCCCUGGCCAUCACGCUCCAGAACAUCGGAGCCAUGUCCAGCUACCUGUACAUCAUCAAGUCUGAGCUGCCACUUGUCAUACAGACCUUCCUGAACCUGGAGGAGAAAACCUCGGACUGGUACAUGAACGGGAACUACCUGGUAAUCCUUGUCUCUGUCACCAUCAUUCUGCCCCUGGCACUGAUGCGGCAGCUUGGCUACCUGGGCUACUCCAGCGGCUUCUCUCUUAGCUGCAUGGUGUUCUUCCUAAUUGCAGUCAUCUACAAAAAGUUCCACGUGCCCUGCCCACUGCCCCCCAACUUCAACAACACCACAGGCAACUUCAGCCACGUGGAGAUCGUGAAGGAGAAGGUGCAGCUGCAGGUCGAGCCUGAGGCUUCAGCCUUCUGCACUCCCAGCUACUUCACGCUCAACUCACAGACAGCAUACACCAUCCCCAUCAUGGCCUUCGCCUUCGUCUGCCACCCCGAGGUGCUGCCCAUCUAUACUGAGCUCAAGGACCCCUCCAAGAAGAAGAUGCAGCACAUCUCCAACCUGUCCAUCGCUGUCAUGUACAUCAUGUACUUCCUGGCUGCCCUCUUCGGCUACCUCACCUUCUACAACGGGGUGGAGUCGGAGCUGCUGCACACCUACAGCAAGGUGGACCCGUUUGACGUCCUGAUCCUGUGUGUGCGCGUGGCCGUGCUGACAGCAGUCACGCUCACAGUGCCCAUCGUUCUGUUCCCGGUGCGCCGCGCCAUCCAGCAGAUGCUGUUUCCAAACCAGGAGUUCAGCUGGCUGCGGCAUGUGCUUAUUGCCGUUGGCCUGCUCACUUGUAUCAACCUGCUGGUCAUCUUUGCCCCCAACAUCCUGGGCAUCUUUGGGGUCAUCGGUGCCACAUCUGCCCCAUUCCUCAUCUUCAUCUUCCCUGCCAUCUUCUACUUCCGAAUCAUGCCCACGGAGAAGGAGCCUGCAAGAUCCACCCCCAAAAUCCUGGCCCUGUGUUUUGCUAUGCUUGGCUUCUUGCUGAUGACCAUGAGCUUGAGCUUCAUCAUCAUUGACUGGGCCUCAGGGACCAGCCGGCAUGGAGGAAACCACUAGGGUGACCCUCAUCCUGUUCUGUCUACUCACCCUAGCAGCCCUGCCCAGACUCUUCAGCCCCUGCUCCCAUCCAGUGGCCAGUCGGGGGAGGAGAAAGACGCGAUUAACACUGUGGCAUUCAGCCAGGCCCCAUGUCCUCUCUGUGGAAGGUUUUUGUUCAAGAGCCAGGACCAAGGCCCUUGGGCCACUACCCUGCUAGGCUCUGGAGCUGUAGAGGCUUCCUGAACUGGGAGCAGGGUAGGGCUGUCGCCUUAGAUCCCGCCCAAGCCCCUCAUUCCCUCCUUGCACAGAUGCAUACACUGGGGCCCAGCAGCUGCCUCCUGAGGUGACACAGCCUGUAGGAACAUACACAGCUGGGAUCAGCCUGCAGCCAUCCCCCGACCCUGCUGCUAGGCCACGGUCUGCGCCCUGGGGCCUCAUCUCCCCCAGCCCACUUGUUUUCCCCCCUUUUAUUCCCUAGGCCCUUUUCAGACUCCUGGGCCCUUGGAUACUCUUCUCCCAUCUCCCUUCACAGGAUGACACCCUCCCAUACCCCAUAGCUGGGGCCAGCAGGUUCUGCUGAGGGUGGGGCUGGUGUAGGGACCCCCAAGAGACCCCUGUCCUGUCCCUUCACCAGUCCUGGGGAGGCUGGGACUCCCCCUGCCACAAGCCUGGGCCACAGCUCACAUUCCACUGCUGGGAGAAGAAACAGGCCGAGGCCCAGAGUGGCCUGCCCCCGGGAGCCAAAGACCCCAGUGGCCACACUGGGAUAGGGUGGGGAGGCUGGCAGCCCUCUUUUAUAAAUAUUAUACAUAAGACCAGCUGUGUUUUCUAUUCUUGGUCUCCAUGGUCCCUGGAUUCCUGGAAAGUGAGGUACGGGCCAGAACAUGGAUGGUGAUGGAGGGCCCCCGUCUCCUUGUCUGGGAUGAGGGUGGGGACAGGGCAAGUCCCCCACCCACCCCACCCCCUGCCUCCCAAACUAACCAGUGGCACACUCAGACCCAGCUCUGGGCCUGGGCCAGGCUCAGCACAGACCUGCUUUCUCACGGGUUGAGGUGGGGAGGAAUUAAUGAGGCCCCAGGAAGUGGGACAGAGAGAGGCCUCCGGAAGGAGGCAACGUGAGGUGCAUCCCCAGCAGCUUCAGGGAGGGUCUGAGCUGGGGGCAGCUGAGCCCUGAGGGAGCCCCAGGAAGGGCCCCCUGCCCUCCCCUAGCUCCCAGGCUGCCAUGUCAACUCUCUGUCAAUGCCCUGAGUCUGGGGACAAAAGUCCAGGAAUCCUGUGCCCUGUUGGGCUGAUCUUUUUAUCAACAGUAAAAUCCACUACGAAUAAA